ACAGCGAGCGGAGCCGCGGUCCGGACGGCAGCGCGUGCCCCGAGCUCUCCGCCUCCCCCCGCCCGCCAGCCGAGGCAGCUCGAGCCCAGUCCGCGGCCCCAGCAGCAGCGCCGAGAGCAGCCCCAGUAGCAGCGCCAUGGCCGGGUGGAACGCCUACAUCGACAACCUCAUGGCGGACGGGACCUGUCAGGACGCGGCCAUCGUGGGCUACAAGGACUCGCCCUCCGUCUGGGCCGCCGUCCCCGGGAAAACGUUCGUCAACAUCACGCCAGCUGAGGUGGGUGUCCUGGUUGGCAAAGACCGGUCAAGUUUUUACGUGAAUGGGCUGACACUUGGGGGCCAGAAAUGUUCGGUGAUCCGGGACUCACUGCUGCAGGAUGGGGAAUUUAGCAUGGAUCUUCGUACCAAGAGCACCGGUGGGGCCCCCACCUUCAAUGUCACUGUCACCAAGACUGACAAGAGUGAGUUCCUGAGUCUUACCCUUCCUUUAGCUCCAAGAUCUCUAAUGUACCGCCUUCUGGUAAUCUUGAGGGUGCUUUUUUGUGUGAUUCCCCAACAUGAAGGGAGUCAGACCAGUAUUGUGUUCCUUGUCUGCUGGAUGCUGGAACACGGGAUAGUCCCUCCAUUCUGUCUCAGUUCCUCAUCUUGUAAUUCGAAGUUGCUGAACUGCAUUACCUCUUAAAUUACUUACUGCCUUGAGCUCGGAUUAGAAACUGUUUUCUAGGAGUAUAGGUAGAUUGUUGGGGUCUUGAAUCAUCGAGUUCAUCGUUUGAGUUCUUUUGUUAGAACCUGGAGGUGGCAUGCACAUCCACAGCCCUUUCUAGCCUGAACACAUGAAUCAACAGUCUAUGAGCCUUUGACCCCUAAGUUUUUAGUCUGUUCCUCUCCAGCGUUUAAGCUUGAUUUUCCUCUUUUGAAAAGCCUUAUUGUUUCAGGGUGACUGACAGCCUGCCUGUGUGUGGUGGGGGGGCGGGUUGGGAGAGAUGAGGUUGGGUUACAGCCCCCAGGGCUGGACAGCUGCUGAACAGCUGGCAGGGGGUGGAAUUGUGACACCUGGAUCCUAGCCUCCUUUCUCUUUCCUCCUCCUCCAGCGCUAGUCCUGCUGAUGGGCAAAGAAGGUGUCCACGGUGGUUUGAUCAACAAGAAAUGUUAUGAAAUGGCCUCCCACCUUCGGCGUUCCCAGUACUGACCUCGUCUGUCCCUUCCCCUUCACCGCUCCCCACAGCUUUGCACCCCUUUCCUCCCCAUACACACACAAACCAUUUUAUUUUUUGGGCCAUUACCCCAUACCCCUUAUUGCUGCCAAAACCACAUGGGCUGGGGGCCAGGGCUGGAUGGACAGACACCUCCCCCUACCCAUAUCCCUCCCGUGUGUGGUUGGAAAACUUUUGUUUUUUGGGGUUUUUUUUUUCUGAAUAAAAAAGAUUCUACUAACAA